UCUUAUUUUUUCUUUUUCCACCCCUUUUCACAGGUGUUGAUCACUUCACAUUAAAAACAACAAUAUACAACUUAAAAGAUGCUAACACUUUACACUUUACUAAGCAAUAAAUUUGUACUUUCUUUUUUUUUUUUUUUUUGAGACGGAGUCUAGCUCUGUCACCCAGGCUGGAGUGCAGUGGCAUGAACUUGGCUCACUGCAAGCUCCGCCUCCCGGGUUCACGCCAUUCUCCUGCCUCAGCCUCCCGAGUAGCUGGGACUACAGGCGCCCGCUACCACGCCCGGCUAAUUUUUUCUAUUUUCUAGUAGUGACAGGGUUUCACCGUGUUAGCCAGGAUGGUCUCGAUCUCCUGACCUUGUGAUCUGCCCGCCUCAGACUCCCAAAGUGCUGGGAUUACAGGCGUGAGCCAAAGCGCCCAGCCUAUUUUCUUUAUUAUUAUUUUUCUGUAGAGACAGGGUACUGCUAUGCUGCCCAGGCUGGUCUCAAACUCCUAGCCUCAAGUGAUCCUCCCAUCUUGGUCUCCCAAAGUGCUGUGAUUACAGGCAUAAAUAAGCCACCACACCUAGCCCAAAUUGGUAUUUUAUAAAAAGUUUUGUUAUUAAAACAAUAAUUACAUUCAACUAUGAAAUCAUUUAAGAAUAUUUCCUAAUAAAGAAGCAUUCAGGCUUGUAAUCCCAGCACUUUAGGAGGCUGAUGGAGGUGGAUCACUUGAGCUCACGAGUUCAAGACCAGCCUGGGAAACAUGGAGAAACCCUGUCCCUACAAAAAAUUCGAAAAUUAGCCAGGAAUGGCAGCAUGUGCCUGUAGUCCCAGCUACUUGGGAGGCUGAGGUGGAAGGAUCGUUUGAGCCCGGGAGAGGGAGGCUGCAGUGAGCUGAGAAAGCACCACUGCACUCCCGCCUGGGUGACAGCCAGGCUCUAUCUCAAAAAAAAAAAAAAAAAAAAAAAAAAAAACACUGAUGGUAAAGGGACAAUAAAAUACACAUAAGCAUACAGUCAGAAGAUUAUUUUUAGAAUUUUACAUAGGUUUGUUAUUAAUGACUAGUGUCAUUAAUGAAUACUUAUCAUUUAAUUGGUAAUUUUUAAUAAGCAUAAUGAUCAGUAGUUGUUACAGGUUGAAUAUUUAUCCUAAAUGCUUGGGACCAGAAGUGUUUUGGAUUUUUUUAUUUUUUCAGAUGUUGGAUGCUUACAUUAUAUACUUACUGCCUGAGCAAUCCUAAUUCAAAAAUCCAAAAUCUGAAAUGCUCCAAAGAGCAUUUCCUUUAAGCACCAUAUCACUGCUCAAAAGUUUCAGAUUCUGGAGCAUUUCAGAUUUUUGGAUUAGGGAUAUUCAACCUGUAUUAAUAAUUAGUAAUUGCCAGGCUUAACUUUUCUCCUUUGGUAAAUUAAAAUAGACUCUAAUUGUGAUGAUGUCUGUUGACAUCUUUAGUUGAAGAAAGUUAAAGGAAGCUUUCUUCAAACUAGAAUGUCUGCAUCUCUAGGGUUACAUGAAGACUUUUCAGGGAAUACAUGGGCAUAGACAGUUUUAAGGUAGCAGUUCCUAAUCUGGAGUCAGGUAAAGACUUCAAAGAGAAUUAGAGGUAUUAUUAGGCCCCCAUACUAGGUUUUAUUAUUGAAUGCAUUAAACAUAUAUAAAACCAUUUUGUAGUUAUGAAAAUGUUAUUACAAUUAUUUCAAAACAAUUUUUUCUAUACAUUUUAUUUCAUACAUUUAAAAAUAUUACUCUAAGUAAAUAAAUGAAUAAAUAACUUCUGCCCAUGAGGGAGGAACAAAGAGUGAAUCUGCCCUCUUGCUUUUAACAACUAGAAAACUGAACAAAAUGUAUUAAACACAUUUUUUCAGACAUUGAACAGGCAGCAAGAGCCUUUGACCCCAGUAAGAAAGAGAACAAGAGAACCAGGAUUGCCCCAGAGGCACAUUCCAAACUACAGAGCAUAGAGCAGAAUUCCAAGUAGCUAUCUAGCUGAAUUGAGAAGCUGGAGGGACAAACUGGCAUUCAAGAAUGCGGAGGUAGAUGAAAGUUCUGAGAUACAAUUUCAAAGUGAAUGAAGCUAUGCUGAAGAAAAUGCAAACUGGUCCCCUUCAUGCUCUGUUCCCUGGUCCCACACAUGCUUAUGCAUAGUGUGACACUCCACCAGGUCUGGCAAGAACCAAACUAGAGAGCUAUCAGUUGAAUAGUUUCAAAGUUCACACAAGGCUGCAAAUCAUUUGAUAUCUCAUCAGCCAGAGUAGUGAGUCUUCACUGACCACUAAGACAAUCAGCAGAAACCUGUAAGAACCAUGCCUUAAUAGUGGGGUAAGCCACCCUUAGAGUAAAAGCUAAUCUAAAUCCACUCUAAAAUCAAUUAUCAAAUGACCAAAGUAAUCAUAAAUUACUAAACAGCCUACCAGAACAAAACCCAAUAGUCAUGAAAGACACAUAACAUGCACAAAAAAAUUCAGAUACUAAACAAUGUAACAUUCACAAUAUUCAGCAGGCAAUCAACAACUAUCAGACAUGCCAAGAAGCAAGACGAUGUGACUUAUACAACAGUAGACCCCAACCCCUAGGCCGCCAGAUCAGUACCAGUCCACGGCCUAUUAGGAACCGGGCUGCAGAGCAGGAGGUGAGCGGUAGGCGAGCAAGCAUUACUGCCUAAGCUCCGCCUCCUCUCAGAUAGGUGGCAGCAAUAGAUUCUCAAAGGAGCCUGAACCCUACUGUGAACUGCACAUGCAAGGGACCUAGGUUGUGUGCUCCUUAUGAGAAUCUAACUAAUGCCUGAUGAUCUGAGGUAGAAGAGUUUCACCCUGAAACCAAGCCUCCCAUCCCCCAUCUGUGGAAAAACUGUCUUCCACGAAUCCGGUCCCUGGUGCCAAAAAGGUUGGGGACUGCUGCUAUACAAAGCUCCAAGAAAUUAAAUAAACCACACACAGGAUAAACACAAAGAAACCCAUACAUAGAUAUACCAAAUAGCUGAAAAUCAGUGAUUAAAAGAAAAAUCUUAAAAGCAGCCACAGAAAACAAGUAAAUUACAUAUAAGAACAAAGAUAAGAAUUUCCUCAGACUGGCCAGGCGCGGUGGCUCACGCCUGUAAUCCCAGCACUUUGGGAGGCUGAGGUAGGCAGAUCACAAGGUCAAAAGAUGGAGACCAUCCUGGCAAACAUGGAGAAACCCCAUCUCUACUAAAAAUACAAAAAUUAACUGGGCAUGGUGGUACGCGCCUGUAGUCCCAGCUACUCAGGAGGCUGAGGCAGAAGAAUUGCUUGAACCCGGGAGGUGAAGGUUGCAGUAAGCCGAGAUCACGCCACUGCACUCCAGCUUGGCGAGGGAGCAAGACUCCAUCUCAAAAAAAAAAAAAAAAAAGAAUUUCCCCAAAUUUGGCAGAAACAACACAUGCCAAAGAACAACUGAAUGAGGUCUUUAAACUGCUAAACGAAACUGUCAGCCUAGAAUUCUACAGGUUGGGGAAAAAACUUUCAAAACUCAAUGUGAAAUAAAGACAUCUUCAGAAAAACAACAGAUAAUCACUAUAAAAACUAUUAGAGAUGGGAGGAUCACUUGAGCCCAGCAGUUCGAGAUGAGCCUAGGCAACACAGUAAGACCCCAUCUCUACAAAAAAUAGAAAAAUUAUCCAGGUAUGGUGUCAUCUGACUGUAGUCUCAUCUACUCAGGAGGCUGAGGCAGAAGAAUCAAUUGAGACCAGGAGGUGGAGGCUGCAGUGAGUUGUGAUUGCACCACUGCACUCCAGCCCGGGUGACAGAACAAGACCCUCUCUCUAAAACAAAACAAAACAAAACAAAAAAAACUUAAAGUUUUUAAACCAGAAUAAUAAAAAUAAAAAAUGAUGUGGGUAUAUAAAAUACUUUUCACGUCAUAAUACCUUUAAAAGAUAGCUGAUCAUUUAAAGCAAAAAUAAUAAAAAUGUAUUGUGUUUAUAAUAUAUGCAGAAGAAACUGUAACAAGAAAGAACAGGAGGGGAAAUAUAAGUAUAUUUUUUAAAGAUCCUUACAUUAUAUUUGAGGCAGUACAGUAUCAUUUGAAGGCAGGUUGUGGUAUUUAAAGUUAAAAGAUAUAUACUGUAGACCCUCAAAUAAUAACAAAAUAAAAAUAACAACAAAAUAAUAAAGUGAUAUAACUAAAUUGUAGAGAUAAAAUUUAGUUAGUAAAAAAAACCCUAAAGUAAACUGAAUAUAAAAAGAAGCGGAAAAGAGGAAGGAACAAAAAACAAAUGUGGCAAAUACAAAAUAAAUAGCAAGAUGGUUGACUUAAAUCCAACCAUAUCAAUAAAUUACAUUAAGUGUAAAUAAUUUAAAAUUUCAAUUACAAGGCAGAGAUUAUCAAAUUGGAUAAAAAAGCAAGACCUAACUAUAUGCUGCUUACAAAAACCCACUUUAAAAGUAUAAAAACACAGGUAAAAGAAUGUGAAAGUAUACCAAGCUGGAGUGGCAAUAUUAAUAACAGAAUAAGCUUGAAGACAAAGAAGUCAUUUUGUAAUGACAAAGUUGUCAAUUCACCAAAAAGACAUAACAAUACUAAAUCUGUACACACCCAAUAAGAGAACUUCGAAAUAAAUGCAGCAAAAAGUGGCAGAACUGACAGAAGAAAUAGACAAAUUCAUAAUUAUAGUUGGAGACUUCAAGAGUUCUCACUUAGUAACAGACACAGACGAAGCAGAGAGAAAAAUCAGUAAGGACAGAGACUUCAACAGCACUAUCAAACAACCUGACCUAAAACACACACUCUACAAAUGACAAAUUGUUUUCAUGCAGACAUGUAACAUUCACUAAAAAUGGUUUUCAUGUAGACACGUAACAUUCACUAAAAUGAACUAUAUGUUGGGCUAUGAAAUAAGUCUCAAAAUAUUUAUAACUACUGAAAUAAUACAAACGAUUCUCUUUGACUACAAUAAAAUUAAACUAGAAAUCAAUAAUAGAUUAAAAUAUAUAGAAAAACUGCAAAUAUAUGGAAAUUAAUCAACGCUUUUAAAUAAUCCAAGGGCUAAAAAAGAAAUCACAAAGAAAUUUUUAAAAUAUUUUGAAGAGAAUGAAAAUGAAAAUGAAAAUUUGUGGGUCAUAUCUAAAGCAGUACUUACAAAGAAAUCUAUAGCUGUAAAUGUUUAUAUUAGGGAGUUUAAAAGUCCAAAAUAAUGGUCUAAGCUUCCACCUUAGGAAGCUAGAAAAAGAGAAAAUUAAAAUAAGUAGAAGAGGAGGAAUCAAUGAAAGAGACUGAAUUUAAUGUAAUACUUUAUUUAAUAGAGAAAUGAAAAAGAGGAAAAAAAUCCAAUGAAGUAAAAAAAAAGUUUUGAAAAGAUCAAUGAAAUCAGUAAAACUCUAGCUAUAUUGAUCAAGAAAAUUUUAGCAAGGUGCAAUGACUCAUGCUUGUAAUCCCAACACUCUGGGACACUAAAGCAGGAGGAUCACUUGAGCCCAGGAGUUCAAGACCAGCCCGAGCAACAUAAGGAGACCCUGUUUCUACAAAAACAAAUAAAAUAAAAUGUGCAGGGCAUAGUGGUGUGUGCUUAUGGUCCCAGCUACUUGGGAGGCUGAGGUGGAAGUAUUGCUUAAGCCUGGGAGAUCAAGGCUGCAGUGAGCCAUGAUUGUGCCACUCUCCUCUGGCCUGCGUGACAAAGAGUGGGAUCCUAUUUCAAAAAUAAAAAUAAAAAGAAAGAAAAUAAAAAUUUUAAAAGACACAAAUGACCAAUAACAGAAAUUCUACAGAUUCUAAUUCUAAAGCUUCUAAAUGAAUAGGGUAUAUCAUCAAACAUUUAAGGAAAAAAAUCAUACCAAGUCUACACAAACUCUCCCAGAAAAUAGAAGAGGGGAGGAUACUUUCCAUUUCAUGUUAUGUAGUCAGCAUUACCUUGACAUCAAACCAAAUAAUGCAAUGGCAAUAAAAUUGCAAACCAAUGUCCCUCGUUAAUAUGUAAAAAUCCUUAAGAUAUUAGAACAUCACAUCCAACCCCACGACCAAAUGGGGUUCACUUCAGGAAUGCAAUGUUAAUUCAACUUUUAAAAAUGAAUCCAUGUAAUUCACAUUAACUGAAUAAUGAAAAAAAGCAAGAUAAUCUCAGUAGAGGCAGAAAAAAAACUGACAAAAUUCAAUACCAAUUCAUAAUAAAAACUCUUAGGAAACUAAGAACAGGAAGGAACUUCCUCAACCUGAUAAAUAGCAUCUUUGAAUAAUUACAGCUAACAUUAUAUUUAAAGAUAAAAUACUAACCACUUUUCUCCCUAAGUUUCAGAACAAGGUAAGUAUACCCACUUUUACCACUUCUAUUCAAUAUUCCAGUAAAGGUCCUAACCAAGGCAAUAAAGCAAGAAAAUGAAAUAAAAGGCAUUCGGACUGCAAAGAAAGAAUACAAUUUAUUCCCAAAUGACACAACUGCAUACACAGAACAUCAGAAGGAAUCAAUCUACAAAAUAGCUAUCAGAAUGAAUACAUGAGUUUGGCAAUAUAGUAGAAUACAAGAACAACAUAUUUGAAAAGAUUGUAUUUCUAGGCUGGGCAUAGUAAUUCAUGCCUGUAAUCCCAGCACCUUGGGAGGCUGAAGUGGAAGGAUUGCUUGAGUACAGGAGUUUGAGAUCAGCCUGGGUAACAUAUCAAGACUCCAAAAAGUUUUUAAAAAUUAGCCAGGAGCAGUAGCACAUGUCUGCAGUCCCAGCUACUCAGUAGGCUGAGGUGGAAGGAUCACUUGAACCUGGGAGGUUGAGGACGCAGUGAGCUGUGAUCACACUAAUGCACUCCAGCCUGGGUGACAGGGUGAGACCCUGUCUCAAAAAAAAGAAAAAAAAAAGAAAUUGCAUUUCUAUGUAUUUCUACUAGAAAAUUUAAAAUUUAAAAAUACUGUUUCAAGGGUAUGAAAUACCUAUGAAUAAAUUUAACAAGCUAUGCAAGAUCUAUACAAUGAAAACAAAAUACUGCUAACAGAAACUGAAGAAAACCUAAAUAAAUGGAACGAUAUAUACUGUGAUCAUGAAUUGGAAGAUUCAAUAUGGUUAAUGUGUCAGUUAUCCCCAAUAAUCUAGAAACUCAAUGCAAUUCAACCAGAAUCCCAGCAGGCUUUCUGUAGAAAGUGACAAACUGAUUCUAGAAUAUUACUGUGAGAAGGGAUCCACAGGCUUUACUAAAUUGUCAAAAGGGUCUAUGGCACAAACCAAGGUUUUAAAGCCCUAUCGCUCUCCAAAUUGUCAACUUCCAGGUGUACUCUUUCCUAAAAUUGAUUUGCCUGAGAACAAGUCUAUGUCCUGAAGAUUUUCCUUAACCACUUCUUUGUUCACAAUUUUUUCCCACUUGACUAAAACAAAGUAUUUCUCUCAGCCAUCCCAGUGUUACUGUAGGCCAUUUUCCUAGGUGUAAAAAAAUUUUGUGGGAGGAGGGGGAUGCAAUCUGUAGAUUUAAUUCUAUGAGAAAGCCACUUAAGAGUAAAGCACAAGGAAGUUUGAUAAGAAAUACUAAAGGAGGCUGUACCUUGCUUCUUUCAGGACAGAUGUUAAUAACAACAAGAACCCACGCCUUAUCUACCACAGAACUACAGUUAAGAAGAUGGUUGUCACAGAGAUAUAUAGGAACACAUUUAUUUCAAUUGAUAAACUCCAAGGUUUUGAUAAAGUAAAGCACUAUCACAAUAUACGACAAUUUAGAAAUUAGAUCUUUUGCAACUAUUUAAACUCUUGACAAAAAAACUCCAGCUGUGAUCAACUUAAAAAAUGUGCAAGAGGAGCACAUGUUAUUCAAAAUUAUUGGAUACACAAGCAAAAAUAUUUGAAGACCACUGAUCUCAGGUAGUUUGUAUCCUGUUUUCUCUAUUAACGAAAUUAUACUUAUGUAAAUAUAACCCACUUUCUUCUAUUAAAGAUUUGAACUGUCUGUAAAUGGAAAUGGAGACUGACUUUCCCUUUUUAAUUUAAUGCUGCAUUUUUGUAAGCAGCUAGAAAAUGUUGCUACUGGCAUUAUGAAAACAUUUACUGGCUAUGCCAAGUUGUUCUCUAUGAACAUCUGCUGUUGAUUUUGACGGGAAGGUGAAAGGAUACAAAAUUCUAUUUAAAACCAUACAUAUCUAUUCCUCUAACGCUGCCUGACAAGCUAUAUAUUAAAUGCCGUGCAUCUUGUUAUACACUGAGAAUACAGAGGUUCUUCUUUUUAGGGACUCCGUCCAAUAGCAGACUCAGUCCUCCAAAGAGUUACAGCAAUUAACUUGUGGUAAGAAUGUACAUGCUAUGGAAAUAUUAAGAUGGGCUCAAAACUAUAAAGUAAGGGGGGAAGGAGUAUUCCAGAAGGGAUUAUAAUACCACGUGCCAAGAUAUGUAAGGGAGGAAGACUAUGGUGUGGUCUGCAAACUACAGUUACAUAUGAAAACAAAGCAUAUUUUCAGAAUUGAUAUUCAAAUUUGAGAUGCUAUCCAUCAUCCAGAGUCAACACUGAUGUACGUAUGGCAAAGAACAGGCAUGGAAAUUCAUUUGGUGGUUUAAUAUUUACUGAGUAUCCACUAUGUAUCUGAUACCAUAUGAGAAACUGGGAAGGAAGUAAAUGAAAAAUAAGCUAUGAAAAAUCUUACAUCAAAGGGAGAAGACAGACAAGUAAAACCACCACAGCACUAGCCUACAGAGUGAUAAAACGCUACAGAAUAUACAUGCACAGUGUUAUAGGAACAAAAAGAAGAGGAAUAGAAUGUUUCCCAAAAACAGUAAUGCUAGAGGAGUAAACUGGAUAGAGAAUAGGAGAAUUGUAGGAGUAAAAUCACAAAGCAAAAACCAAGUUCAGUUAAAAGCUGAAGAAAAAGAAGAAAGUAUGGCAAAGGAGGCUAAAAAGCCAGAUCACCAAGGACAUUGAGUAGUAAGAAAUCAAGCUAUGGAAGCCACAGAAGGGUUUCAGGCAUCAGUAAGAUGAUCAAUCACUCUAUCAAGCAGAGUGAAAGAUAUACUAAAGGUGGAGGCUGAGAAUAUGGCAAGACUGAAGAGAACUUCAAUAUGCAAUUCAGGGAUAUUUAUAAUUCAGAAUAUAUAAAAGCAAGAAAAUAAAGGAAAUAUGGUCAAGGAAGAUAGAGAAGAGAUGGUGGGUAAAGGAGGUAUUUCAAAGGUGCUAGUUAUACAGAUAUUUAUUUUGUAUUUACAUGUUAAACUACGUUAUAUACUUUUAUGUGUUAUAUUUCACAUUUUAAACAAAUUUUUAAAGGGAGAAGCGUUGCUGAAUUACAAAAAUAGCAGUGAGAAAGGAGAAGAAAGGAAAAAUUAAGAAACAAGUUAAAACCAAGAGAAGAAAAGAACGAAACUAAGAAUCCUACCCCACCCCCAAUUUCACAGUCUAGGUGGAAGGUGAAGCCAUUUACCAACGACAUAUAGAAGCCAGUUGUUUUAUAGGGGAAGAACUCAACUUGGACAUGUAGAAUUUGAGCUGCCUGAAUGACACUCAGAUGGAGAUAUCUAAUAGGUUUUUAGACAUGCAGGCCAAAAACUUAGAAAAAACCGUCCAGACUGAAAGUAAAAAUUGGUGCACGAUGAGCCAGUAUGGUAGACUAUGGCCUUGAAAAAUAUCACCCAAGAAUACCAUGAAAAUUACAGAAGGCCAAGGACAGAGUAAUCUCCAAGGAGCCUGUAAAAUAAGACCUGAACUUAAACGAGAUUUUGAAUUAUUAGCAUAGCCAUUUGACAUAUAAGAAACCUAAGAGUCCAAAUACCUUUUCUUAAAAUGAUAGCUUUUCAUUUUUCCUUUGAUUAAUGAAGAAAAAAGCCUAUAUUUUCCAAUGACAAAGUUAUAAAUGAUGGAAAUUCUUAGUCAUGUAAGGCAUUUCUCAUUGUACACCAUUUAUUAUAAUUCACUUGAAAUUCAAUCAUCUGCCCUUCCUAAAUUUCAGCCAAAAUAGGAUUUGGGGUAGCUUCAGUAUGAUUCCAAGACUGUGUAUCUCUCUACCAUCUAGCUCAGCCAUCACCUGGCUUUCAAUAGAACCAGCAUGUGAAUCUGUUGUAAUACUAGAUUUUACGUGCACCUGGCAGAAAGUAGGAUGAGUAUUACAGCAUCUGACAGCAGGUAGCUGAAAGGAACUGGCAAUUCUUUCAGUCCUGCCUGCUCAUGAAUUCUAGAUACAGCAAGAAAUGUAACAGGUAAAAUUAUAUUUAUGCUUAACAAAGACUUCCUGAAUUUUCAAAUAACAUGACUACAAACAGUCCUAUACUUCCCCAAGAAUAUAUUUUUACUUUUUUCCCCAGCUUCCCAAGCUUACAAUCCCAAGAAUAAAAUAUUAUAAAGCAGAAUGAGCUUCCAUUUUUGUUGAAGUCACUGCAAUGCAAAUAAAAGGCUUACCGUAAUUACAUCUGGCAAUGAAGUUACAUUUAAUAACUUUCAGUCUCAUGGCACCUAGCAGAGACUAGACUUUCAAAAAGCACAAAAUAAUAGACACUGACUACAAAGAACAACAAUAUAAAACAAAGAAACUCAAAAUAGUUUGCUUUAUCCCUUAAAGGGGCACAAAGGUCUGAGAUUUGUAUGUAAAUGCCUGAAAAUAAGAGAAUACCAUUUAUAUCAUCAUUUAUAGUUAUUCAAUGAAUUUUUGUAAUUCUAAUUAAGAAUUACAUUCAAGAAUUACAUUCAGAAGACAUGAAAUACGGUUAAAUACUUCACAAAAUCUGGGGGAAAAUACGUGUGCUUAUACUCCCAUAUGCAGUACUUACCUGUUUGUAUCUAAAGAAAGAUGAUCUUAAGAUAUAUUCUCUCUCUCUUUUUUUUUUUUUUUUUUUUUUGCUGCUCUGCAAGGAGCAGGGCUAACUUUAAGGCCAGAGUUGGCCUUAAGAUGUAUUCUUGAAAUAUACAUUUCUGCUUGUGGGAGCACUCAGAGAUUACUAGAAGUUUUUUAAAAGAAAGUUUUCAAAAACUGGAUAAUGCUCUUCUUUGUUCUAUACAGAAAUCAUGUUUAAUCUUAUACAGAACAAAGAUUAAACCAGCUGAGUAUAAUCAUUCUCUUUACAAUUACAAAGAGUAUCUAAUUAUCAGACAUAGUUAAGCCAGAACAGAUUACAGAAGACAAGCCUGAUUUUAAAAACGAACAUAAAAAACUGAAAAGACUUAGCAAUGUACAGCCAAGUUAGUACACAAAUUAUUGGGUACCUACUAGAUGAAAAGCACCAUGCUAAAUGCAGGGGGAGAAACAAGAAGUAAAACAUUCAGUUUCUGUCACUGGUCACAAAUUUUAAGACCACUGUACAAUAAGAUUUAAGAUUUAAAAAGCAACAUGAGGCCAGUGGCUCAUGCCUGUAAUCCUAGCACUUUGGGAGGCCAAGGCAGGAGGAUCACUUGAGCUCAGGAGUUCGAGACCAGCCUGGGCAACAUAGUGAGACCCUGUCUCUAUGUAAAUAAAAAUAUUAAAAAAAAAAAAAAAAAGAAAGCAACAUGAAAUUUCAGGCAACAUACGCUUAAAUAUCAAAUUAGUAAUUUAAACAAUAAGUAAGAUCUGAGGAAAGAUUACAUCCAAGUUUUUUGAAGCUACUUCCAGCCCAUGUAUUUAGUGAACUAUAGUUUUUACAACAAGAAGUUAAUCAGAUUCUUGAAAUUAUUGUAAUUUUUUUUUAAAGCAGUAGCAGAGGGGUGACAGUUUCUCACUAUUCAGGCCUUCCAGCUAGAGAAGAGGGACAAGGAAUAACUGAGUAGGAAAUUAGAUUAAAUGAUCACUUCCUUAAAGUCUACAGUUCUUCCUUAAUUUAAGAAAGUAUAAAAUCUCGGCCAGGCGCGGUGGCUCACGCCUUUAAUCCCAGCACUUUGGGAAGCCGAGGCGGGUGGAUCACGAGGGUCAGGAGAUCGAGACCCUCCUGCCUAACACGGUGAAACGCCGUCUCUACUAAAAAUACAAAAAAUUAGCCAGGCCUGGUGGUGGGCGCCUGUAGUCCCAGCUACUCGGGAGGCUGAGGCAGGAGAAUGGCGUGAACCUGGGAGGCGGAGCUUGCAGUGAGCCGAGAUCGCGCCACGGCACUCCAGCCUGGGUGACAGAGUGACACUCCGUCUCACAAAAAAAAAAAAAAAGUAUAAAAUCUCAAAUACAAUGUAUGAAAACAAACUCAUAAAACACAAGUACUGUCUAAGACAGUGGUUUUCAAAUUCUGGUGAACAUCUAAAUAACCUGGAUAACUUCUUAAACCACAUAGAUGCCUAGGUAGUAUCUCAAACCUUUGGAAUCGGAACCUAUAAAGGUGAAGUAUAUCUGUAUCCUGAGAAAGCUCCGUAAGUGAUUCUGAUGAACAGCAAAGUGUUAAAAUUAAGUUACAUGGUUAAGUACACACUCUUCAGUGGUAAGGAAAUCUGAGUUCAAAUGCCAAUUCUAAUAUUUACUAGAGCCAUCACCAACUAACUACCCACCCUAACACUAUUUCUAAUCUACAAAAAGGGGAAAAGCUAGCUAUACCUCAAGUGAUUGUUAUAAGGAUUAACAGUGAUGAUAAGAUAAAAUGUUUAGUACAAUUCUUGGCCCAUUCAGUAAGCAUUAAAUGAAUUCAUUCAUUUAAUAAACAUUCAGCACUUACACAUCAGGAGAUGAGGAACAUCUAAUUAAUUUAUUAAGUAUUAAUAAACAUGACAACUCUUCAAUGGUGUGGUAAGAACAUAUAAUCAGGAGAAUGUAUUCUAAUCAGGAAAGUCUUCCCUGAAGUGAGCUGAAUGAUGAAUAGGCAUAAUUGGCUAAAAAAAGAAAGGAAGGGCAUUUCCAAGCAGAGGAAGUAGCAUAACCAAAGCCACAUACUUGAAGCAGGAGAACAGAAAAGACAGGGUGACUAGGGGAGAAAGGGAAUGUCAGAAAGCACAGUGGAGAUGAGUUUGGAAAGGGGACCGACUAUGCAGGGCUUGUAGGGCAUGUUAAUGUGUUCGAUUUACUUAAAAAUGGUGAGAAGCCACUGAAAGAUUUUAAACACUAAGACAAUGUUAUUAGGUCUGCAUUUUGAAAAAGUCACUAAGUCUUGUUUGGAAAACUACAGGAGACCACAGUAGAUGCAAGCAGACCAUAAUCAGGAGGCUACGGAAGUAGUCAGGAUGAGAGAUGGUGGUGGCUUGGAACAGGACUACUGUUACAGACGAAGAGCAGACAAGAGUCAAGAGAUAUUCAAGAGGCAAAAUCAACAGGACUUCAUGAGAGGCUGAGUAUGAAGCACGACAGAGGAAUUGUCAAACUUCAACUUCUAUACAAAGGAAUGGAUAGUGAUGCUACCCACGGAGUUAAACACAGUAAGAGGAGCUAUUUUUCUUCUUGGGGUGGGGGAAGGGAGGUAUAUCAUGAAUUUCAAACAUGUGAAUAUGAGUAGUUAUUCCCAGUAACAGGGUUGAUCUGUCUAGAAAGUAUUCCACAGUAUAGAAGUACAAUGUGCCUGUAUUUAUUUUACUGGGUAUUUAUGAAUCUUAGAGACAAAAUAGGUUUCUGCAUGUGAGUAAUGUAAAUCUAAAGAGAAUGAAGGCCCUUACCUUCCAUUAGGUUCCCUUCCUUUACACAAUCCCCCAAAAGCAUUCUUUAUGAUUACAGUUUAAUGUUGCCUCAAGAAGUAAUUUAUAUACUCAGCUGAUUUCAUUUUUAAAUAUUUUAAAAAUAUUUGUGCUAAAGAAUAAGACAGCAAACCAAACAACAACAAACCUGCAAAGUCCAAAAGGAAUCUUCAAGCACCUGACUUUCAAGCCAUCACCAGAACAUAAUGGGGUUUUACAGUGGCAGGCUGAUUUGGAGCAUUUUUGCUAAACUAUUUAUUUUUCAGAACGGAGAUAGGCUACUUAGAAAACUCACUCAUAGUAUCCAAUGUUUUUAGAAAGUGUCAUCACAAAUAAUUCCUGAGUUUGACGUACUAAAAAAUAGUUGACACCUUCCAAUGAAGUCACUACAGGCAUAGCGCUUUUAAGCAGCUUGUCUGGAGCCUCCUCGAGUGCCUUAGAGGGUGGAUUUGAUAAUAUGGCCUCCUUAAUUACGGAUCACAGGUAUGUGCUCAAAGUCCAAUAAGUUUUUGCAAGCUUUAUCGGUCUAAACCCUCCUCCAUCCGUAUUCUCCCGUUUAGAAAAACAAGACUGCAGGAGUAACCGUGGGGUUUUUUCUCUUAACAAAACCCCUGCCCCACCCACCUCACACACAAUAACCUUCCAUUCCAGAACUAAAGCUACUGUCAGAGAAGGACGGCGGGCGGCAGGGCCCUGGCUGGUGACCCAGGCUACCGGAUUCCGGACCUCAGAACUGAGGAUGCUCUGGUCCUUUUCAAGCUACUCAGCUAUGGGAUGGUAUUAUUCACUCUCUUCAGGCCCAAGUGGAAAUAAAAAGAAGGAGGCAUCAUUUACAGACAUACAAAGACUGUUUCACUGGUUCUGAUGCUGUCGAUGUGGUCUUAAGUCAUCUUAUGCAAAACACGUGCCUAAGUAGCAAUGACAUCUCUUGUCUUAAAGGGGUUCAUCUUUGCCAAGUUCUAAUGAAUCACAAAGUAUUUGAACCAGUAGGAAUGAAGAAGCUUUUCAAAAAAGAAAAGGAAUUAGAAUUUGAAGAUUCCAACAUUAGUCUCUACAGGUUUCUAGGCAAUAAAUCAUCUUACGAUUGUUGCAAAAGACAAAAGGAUGCUGAGAAUGAGUUCAAUGAAACCUUGAGACCAGGAUAUGAAAUGAUUUCAAAUCCUCUAGCACAGGAGAUUGGUGAGGAAAGAAUUGAGGAACUUAUUCAUACAAUAAAUGGGAAUCCAGCUUUAUGUCCAAAUAUCACAGUUCAGAAACCUUUUCUCCGGCUUUCAAAAGAAGGAGUUUCCUUCUACACAGCAAUUACAUCAGAUAAGACAGAUGUUUGGAAAGAACAAACAUUAUUAUGUCUUCUUCAAUUGAUUCACCUUCCAUUCUUGGACAAUAUUUUGGAGCCUCCAGUUAAAACACAAAAUCUUCAACUAAACAAAGAGGAAGAUCUUGUUAUCACUAACACUUGCCUAGACAGAGAACUUAUUCCAAGCUUAUGUCUACCUGAAAUCGAUAACUGGCUUAAUGCAGCAAUUGAAUGCUUGGAGUAUUUCCCUGACCAGUUAAUAGUUACAGUUAGUCAGCAGUUAAUGCAAAACAGAAAUGAAGAGACAAGAUUGAACAGUCAGAAGAAGAUACUCUUUGAUGUCAUAGCAAAAUACUAUGCUCAAGAGAGAGAUUGCCUAUUAACUGAUGAGUAUUUUGAUAUUCAUUCAGGAAUUAUUGAACUUUUAGAAAAUGAGAAAAGAGCAGAAGCACUUGAAGCAACACAACUAUAUCUAAGAUUGCUGUUGCUGAACAUUAGAGAAGAAUUACGACGGCUACUUACUUUUAUGGCAAUGGCAUCAGAGCCCAAUGCCUACAAGUUGCAAAAACAGUAUGAUAAUAAAACAGUGGUCCUGAAAACUCUUGCCAAAUCAGUUUUGCAAGCCAAAUCAUUAUUAAAAGUGCGGGCAGAACAACUGGUCUGGUUUCCACUGGAGUACCACUCUGAGCUCUUCAAGACACCAGUUACUUUAUUGGAUCUGGUUAGUAAGAAACUUAAGAAGCUUCUACAUGGAGAAGAUGCAGAUGCCAUAUCAGUUGGGGAGGAAGUUAGUAUACUUCCAGUGGAAGACCUGAGAGGGUACCUGAAGAGAUACCGGGAAAAUAUUGGAAACAUGCCACCAAGCCCUCUUCGAUAGAAGUCUCCUUAUUUGGAAAGUUGCCAUUUUAAUGUUCAGUGUGAAUCAGGUAGGGAUUUGCUAGUCAUCACUAUGAAUGGUGGAUACUUUGACAAAUGCUUUAAGGAUAUUACCAUGUUGUUGCGUCUGCUGUUCAGAAAAUUAUAACCUUAGACAAAUAUCUUUGCACUGAGCCUCAGUUUUUUAAAAAUCUCUAAAAUAAAAAUACACAUGCACAGA